GUAAAGACUAGGGCGCCAGCGGCUGGCGAAGAAGGAAAGAGGGUACUCUCUGGCUGGGCUGGGGCCGUAGCGACGUCCGCCGCGAACCUGGGCCCCCCAAAGCUGCGGGGCGUUCGGUGUCGCCGAAGUAAACAUGCACCCUGAGCCCUCGGAGCCUGCGACAGGUGGUGCAGCAGAGCUGGAUUGCGCGCAGGAGCCCGGCGUGGAGGAGUCUGCGGGUGACCACGGGAGCGCAGGCCGAGGGGGCUGCAAGGAAGAAAUUAAUGAUCCUAAGGAAAUAUGUGUGGGUUCUUCUGACACAUCCUACCACAGCCAGCAGAAACAGAGUGGUGAUAAUGGGUCAGGUGGUCACUUCGCACACCCAAGAGAAGACAGGGAAGAUCGGGGCCCCAGAAUGACUAAAAGUUCCCUGCAAAAACUCUGCAAGCAGCACAAGCUUUAUAUUACCCCAGCAUUGAAUGAUACGCUGUAUUUACACUUUAAAGGUUUUGAUCGCAUUGAGAACCUGGAAGAGUACACAGGGCUGCGCUGUCUCUGGCUGCAGAGCAAUGGAAUACAGAAAAUCGAAAACCUGGAGGCCCAAACUGAGUUGCGUUGCCUCUUCUUGCAAAUGAACUUGCUCCGUAAAAUUGAGAACCUGGAACCUCUGCAGAAACUGGAUGCUCUUAACCUCAGCAACAAUUACAUCAAGACCAUUGAAAACCUCUCCUGCCUCCCAGUCCUGAACACAUUGCAGAUGGCCCACAAUCACCUGGAGACCGUGGAGGACAUUCAGCAUCUACAAGAGUGUUUGAGGCUUUGUGUCCUUGACCUUUCGCACAACAAGCUGAGUGACCCGGAGAUCCUGAGCAUUCUGGAAAGCAUGCCCGAUUUGCGUGUACUGAAUUUGAUGGGAAACCCGGUUAUCAGACAGAUUCCUAAUUACAGAAGGACAGUCACUGUACGACUAAAGCACUUAACAUACCUGGAUGAUAGACCAGUGUUUCCAAAGGACAGAGCUUGUGCGGAGGCCUGGGCUAGGGGAGGGUACGCAGCUGAAAAGGAGGAGAGACAGCAGUGGGAGAGCAGGGAGCGGAAGAAGAUCACAGACAGCAUUGAAGCCUUGGCCAUGAUCAAGCAGCGGGCAGAGGAGAGGAAAAGACAGAGAGAGAGUCAAGAGAGAGGUAUGCGCUCGGCCGAAGACAACAGCCCCAGAGUUCCUUUGAGAUUAGGGGAGAUGACAUCUUCAGAUGAUGGUGAGAAUGUGCCCGCCAGUGCGGAAGGCAAGGAGGAGCCUCCCGGGGACAGAGAAACAAGGCAGAAGAUGGAGCUAUUUGUUAAGGAAAGCUUUGAGGCCAAGGACGAGCUCUGCCCGGAAAAGCCAAGUGGAGAGGAGCCGCCUGUGGAGGCUAAAAGAGAGGAUGGAGGUCCAGAGCCAGAGGGGACCCUCCCAGCUGAGACCCUGCUACUGUCGUCACCUGUGGAGGUUAAAGGAGAGGACGGAGAUGGAGAGCCAGAGGGGACCCUCCCAGCUGAGGCCCCACCACCCCCGCCACCUGUGGAGGUUAAAGGAGAGGAUGGAGAUCAAGAGCCAGAGGGGACCCUCCCAGCUGAGACCCUGCUACUGUCACCGCCUGUGAAGGUUAAAGGAGAGGAUGGAGAUCGAGAGCCAGAGGGGACCCUCCCAGCUGAGGCCCCACCACCACCGCCCCUGGGAGCUGCCAGGGAAGAACCGACUCCCCAGGCUGUGGCCACUGAGGGUGUAUUCGUUACAGAACUUGAUGGAACGAGAACGGAAGAUUUAGAAACCAUUAGACUGGAGACAAAGGAGACAUUCUGCAUUGAUGACCUACCUGACUUGGAAGAUGAUGAUGAAACAGGCAAAUCUCUGGAAGACCAGGUUAAGAGGCCAUUACUGGCAUUACCAGGAGCCCACACGUGCCAGACCCGUACCCUGAGGGAGAAGGAGGCAUCAGCCAUCAUCUCUGAGCACGAGCUCAGCAGCAAAGAAAACAGACACAGUUACUGUGGGGGGCCUGCUGUCCAAGGAGCUAAGUCCCAGAGAGUCUGUGAAGGAAACGGGGUUCAGGGGCAUGCCAAGCAGAGCCCAGGGCUCAGGGGUGCGCCCUCUCAGGUACCAGGAGGGUGAGGAAUAGCCAGUGGCUGGGGGAGCAGAGGGCAGAGAGAAGGGCAUAGACAUGAGCUGUGCCCAGGGAGUGGCCACCCCCAGGCCUAACUUUCAGAGUCCUGUGUUCCCUUGGGCCUUUCUUGGAUGUGGCAACAGAAUACUUUGUGACAUUGGGUGAAAAAGCAGAACUGGCAUGGUGCAUUGUAGAGCGAUUCUGUUGUGAAAACAGAAACUUUCAGACACCUUUUCUUCUGUAAAUAGAAUAUGUGCUUUCCGAAGAUUGAGGUCAUCUCGAGCUUGAGUGAUGACAGUGACCCUGAACUGGACUACACGUCACUCCCUGUGCUGGAAAACCUCCCCACAGACACUCUGUCAAAUAUAUUUGCAGUCUCUAAAGACACCUCAAAGGCGGCUCGGGUGCCCUUCACAGACAUCUUUAAAAAAGAAGCUAAGAGGGACUUGGAAAUCCGAAAACAAGACACCAAGUCCCCAAGACCCCUGAUCCAGGAGCUCAGCGACGAGGACCCCUCUGGCCAGCUACUGAUGCCCCCCACCUGCCAAAGAGAUG